GCUGGAGUGCAGUUGUGCGAUCUCGGCUCACUGCAACCUCCACCUCCCGGGUUCCAGUGAUUGUCCUGCCUCAGCCUCCCAAGUAGCUGGGACUACAGGUGUGCACCACCACGCCCAGCUAAUUUUUGUAUUUUUUAAGAGAGACAGGGUUUCACCAUAUUGGCCAGGCUGGUCUCAAACUCCUGACCUCAUGAUCCUUCCACCUCAGUCCCCCAAAGUGCUGGGAUUACAGAUGUGAGCCACUGUGCCUGGCCAUACCUAUUUUUGUUUUUAAUGCUUUAUAGGAGCAUAUAAACACAAACAUUUUCUUUUUGUCUUUCCAAAUUCUGUGCUUUAUUUAGCCUUUGCUAUUAACUGCAUUUUGUCAGUUUUCUGCCAUUUAAUCUACAUUACAACCCAGUGAAUUAGAAAGGGCAGAUAAUUUAAUUCCUAUGUUUAAAAAUCAGAAACUAAAAUUUAGAUUAAAUGUUUUGCUUGGGGCUGCACAUCUAAUCAAAGGAAAAGCUGAGACUAGUACUGACUUUUUAACAUUGUUCUUGUCAGAACCACACUGAGUAAAAAAGGUAGCUCCUUCAUUGUUUCUACAUAUCACACUUGAAUUUAACUUCCAUGUGAAAAAAACAUGUGUAUACAUUUGACCCAAGUAACUAUAAGUUAAGAUGAAUUCCUGUUCAUUUUCUUCAUACUCAGUGUGCCUAGGAUAGCGAGUGUAGAGUAAUAAGUAAAAUUGUGAAAUUGAGCAGCGUAUUAGUCUGUUUUCACACUGCUAUAAAGACAUAUAAUUACUGGGUAAUUUAUAAAGAAAAGAGGUUUAAUUGGCUCACAGUUCCACAUUGCUGGGGAGGCCUCAGGAAACUUACAAUCAUGGUGGAAGAGGAAGAGGCAUGACUUCAUGGUGGCAGGUGAGAGAGACUGAGCAAGAGUAGGGAAAACUGCCUUGUAAAACCACCAGAUCUUCUGAGAACUCACUAUCACAAGAACAGCAUGGGGGUAAAAAUACCCCUUCAUGAUUUAACCACCUUCCACCUGGUCCUUCCCUUGAUACAUGGGAAUUAUAGGGAUUAUAAUUCCAGAUGAGAUUUGGGUGGGGACAUAGAGCCAAACCAUAUUAACAAGGAAUGUUCUGAAAGAAAGGAAAAUUGUAAGGUGGUGGAAUGUUUAGUUAUCCAAAUCAAAGCAGAGUCUACUUGUAGGCACUUUAUUUUUAGAAAAUAAUCACUUCUUAUUUAUUAUCAGCAGGUUUCUACCAUAAUUCGCAAAUGGCAAACACUUCAGAAGUUUAUAAUAAAAAAAGUGACUUUUUAGACUAGCUUAAUGAGUAGUCUAGCCUUUCUCUUGUAAAUGUCAAACUUACAUAAUUGAGUUUUGCUAGCUUCAUAAUAUUGUUGAUGGCAUGAUAUGUUGUUUAUGCAUUCUGUUAUUACAAAACAUUAAAUAGAUUUGUCAACAAGUUGUGGCAAACAAAUUAUAAUUUAAUCUCUUUGUGAAUUUUAUUAUGUGGAGGAGGAAAAAUUGGAUGUUUUCCUCCUUGUUGAUUGACAUGUAGAACACUCAUGCCCUGCUCCAAUGCCUGUCAUCAUUUAAAGAAAAAAGAAAAAAAGCACACAAAACAAAGAUAGGAUACUGUGUCUGUUGAAUGAAAAAUAAGAAUUUUUUCAUUCUAUGUACUUCACGUUAAUUUUAAGAGCAUAUGCAUUUAUUUAAAAGUUAAGAAAGUAUAUUAGUGAUCUAAGAUAUUUCGAAGUAAAUAGAAUUGUAUUAGGUUAUUUUUUGCAAUAAUUUUGUUAAGUAAAAGGAAUUUUAAAAUUUUUAUUUGUAACAUUGGUUUUUAUAUGGUAUUAACAUUUCUGAAAUUGACUUAUGUAUCCUGUAUAGCACCCUAAACAUUUAUUUUAAAACAAAUCAGUAAAAAGUAACAUAGAAUCCCUUUCCAAAUCAUGGUAAGUGAGCAUGUUUUUAAAACUCUUUGUUUUUACCUGCAAGGGAAGGAGAUAACAGAUUGAUUGAUAAUGUGCAUGCAUAAGUAUGCCUUAUAACCAAAUGUAGAAGUGUAUGUGAGCUGUGGAGUACUCCUCCCCAAAAUCUGUCAAAACAUAACCUGAAAUCUGGUUUUAAACCUGAAAGUGGUUUUGAGAAUUUAUUAUUAUUAUUUUAAUACAAUAGAUUCUGCAUUGGAUAUUUCCAAAGGCAGUAAAUAUUUUUGUAAUUGUUAUUAAUGACCAUUGGUAAGCUGUUGGUGAUUAAAUUUUGGCUCUAAUGACUUCAGGCUGUUUGUCAUAUACUAUAUUUAAUAAAGAAAAAGGUAUCUGGGAAAUUCUUAACUUCUCUAAUGUUAUCUUGGAGCAUAAAAUCUUACUGAGUUGAGUGUUGUAUGUUUAGUGAAUCAUUUUACACCAGCUAGAAAGACAGAUGGGUAGUGUGCAGUUUAAAUAUCUGUGCAAAUGAGAGGACAGAUGGGUGGUUUAAAUGGUUUAAAUGUCUCAAUGAAAAUGUGUAGAGAGAUUGUCUUCUGAAGUUAGACUAAAAAAUUCAGGGAAUUAAUUAGGAAUAAUAGUUAAUAUAACAAAAUAAAAUUUUUAAAUAAGAGGCAAAAUAUGGAAUUCAGUGAAUUGAUUAUACCUUUUGAACUGACAGUAAAAAGUAACAUCUUAGAACACAGUACUCAAAUACACUUGCAUGGUAACUGCCUGUUUUGUUUUCUUAUUAUGAACAUGUGGACUGUGGAAAGUGUCUUUAUUACUUGGAAUUAACUUAUCUGGUUAAUUGUACCUGACCUUUUGAACUGUUGUCAGAAUUAAUUUGUUCAAUUUCAAGUAGUUAACAGAAACUUAAACUAGCUUAAAAAUGGUGAGUAAAAAAAAAAACCAGACUAAAAACCAAAAACCUUGAAAUGGGCCUCAGAAAAGGCAGCUUCUGUAGCAGGAGUUAGUGAACUUUUACUCUUAUUCAGGAAUUAAUAUGACUUAGCUUCUAGCCAAAAUAUUGGUUCCUAUAUUGUCAGGUAUGUACCUUAGAUCUUGGAUGUCAGCUCCAUGUAGGAGCCUCCUCCUAACUUGUGUGGGUGGGGACAAAAAGGGGUGAUCACUUUUAGAUGGAAGGCUGUGGGCUGGCCAUAGAUAUGUCAGUUGCACUGACCUUUUUUUUUGUUUGUUUGACAGAGUCUAGCUCUGUUGCCCAGGCUGGAGUGAAGAGGCUUGAUCUUGGUUCACUGCAACCUCCGCCUCCUGGGUUAAAGUGAUUCUCCUGCCUCAGCCUCCCGAUUGGCUGGGACCACAGGCAUGCACCACCACACCUGGCUACUUGUUUUGUAUUUUAGUAGAGAUGGGGUUUCACUGUGUUGGCCAGGCUGGCCUCGAACUCCUGACCUCAAGUAAUCCGCCCGCCUCGGCCUCUGAAAGUGUUGGGAUUACACGUGAGCUGCUGCACCCAGGCAAUUGCAUUGACUUUUGGGGACUUUUAAUGAAAUAUAUUCUGUAAGAAGAAUGCUAAGUAGUAAUAUUCAUGGAUAAAAAUGCUAUUGUAUUAUUCUAUGAAAAAUUAUUAGUAACUGAUCAUGUGGGAGGAUAUGUUCCUUAGAACAUUAAAAAUCAUUCAUGGUUAGUAUUACUGAAGUUAUUUUAUUAAUUGCUAAGUUAAAAAAUUGUGCCAAGUGUCAUGCAGAGUGAGAUAAAUCUUCUCUAGGGAUUUAUUUUAACUGAGGCAAAAAAUUUACUGAUUUCUGAUAAACAUUAAAAAAAUUCAAAUAGAUUAGAAUUUUUGAAAAAAUCACUGGGCAUACCUCAUAGUAAGGAGAAUAAUCAUUUUAUAUUACAUUUAUAUAAACACAUAUUUGAUUAUUUACUGGUUCAUGACAUAAAAUAUAUUAUCUUGUGGGUGGUAGUCAAAAAGUUUGAAAAGUAUUACUUUAGUGAUUCAAGUUUUUUUCUUUCUUUCUGAUUUUCUUCAGGUGAGAACUAAAUUAAUGUACUUGCUUCCCUCCUGCCACUCUAGUUUUAGAACAUGUUUCUCUUCAGCAGUGACAGGGGUUAGAGAUACUCAGGUGAAAAGAUUAUUUUCUUAUUAAGAAGUUCUUUAUGUUAUAAAGUGAAAUAGAUUAUCUGGGUAACAUUUUGUUAAAAACUUGGACAGUUAUUAAUAUCCUCAUGUGCAAGAGCCAGUGAAUGGACAAUGGGUACAGAAUUAAACUCUUUAAAAAAAUUAUGUGUUGCUCCAUAGAAGUCAGUGGUGAUUCUAGUAUUUGUGAACUCUAGAAUUUAUUGAUAGUAGAGACAUACAAGUCUGCCAGAAGGUUUGUUUCUGUUUAUACGAUGUGGAUGUAGUUCCUGAGCAUCAGAAUUGGAGGGAUGAUGAGAAAGCAAGGGAAUUCUAUUUCUCAUUCUGUUGUUCUUCCUAGGAAUGGUCUGAGGUCUGAAAUUGUCCCUCUUUGCAAAAACCCUCACCUUUUCUCUGCUCUUUGCUCUGGGGUACUGAGAUUCUUAAAUGAGGAAUACUCAGAUGGUUGCUGAGCCUAAGCAGAAUGGCAACAGAAGGGAGCCUGCCGUCAAAAAUUCUCAACUUAAGAUCUGUUUCUGUUUCAGCUUUCUACAUAUGGCUAGCCAGUUUUCCCAGCACCAUUUAUUAAAUAGGGAAUCCUUUCCCCAGUGCUUGUUUUUGUCAGGGUUGUCAAAGAUCAGAUGGUUGUAGAUAUGCGGCAUUAUUUCUAAGGGCUCUGUUCUGUUCCAUUGGUCUAUAUCUCUGUUUUGGUACCAGUACCAUGCUGUUUUGGUUACAGUAGCCUUGUAGUAUAGUUUGAAGUCAGGUAGCAUGAUGCCUCCAGCUUUGUUCUUUUGGCUUAGGGUUGACUUGGCAAUGUGGGCUCUUUUUUGGUUCCAUAUGAACUUUAAAGUAGUUUUUUCCAAUUCUUUGAAGAAAGUCAUUGGUAGCUUGAUGGGGAUGGCAUUGAAUCUAUAAAUUACCUUGGGCAGUAUGGCCAUUUUCACGAUAUUGAUUCUUCCUACCCAUGAGCAUGGAAUGUUCUUCCAUUUGUUUGUAUCCUCUUUUAUUUCAUUGAGCAGUGGUUUGUUGUUCUCCUUGAAGAGGUCCUUCACGUCCCUUGUAAGUUGGAUUCCUAAGUAUUUUAUUCUCUUUGAAGCAAUUGUGAAUGGGAGUUCACUCAUGAUUUGGCUCUCUGUCUGUUAUUGGUGUAUAAGAAUGCUUGUGAUUUUUGCACAUUGAUUUUGUAUCCUGAGACUUUGCUGAAGUUGCCUAUCAGCUUAAGGAGAUUUUGGGCUGAGAUGAUGGGGUUUUCUAAAUAAACAAUCAUGUCAUCUGCAAACAGGGACAAUUUGACUUCCUCUUUUCCUAAUUGAAUACCCUCUAUUUCCUUCUCCUGCCUGAUUGCCCUGGCCAGAACUUCCAACACUAUGUUGAAUAGGAAUAGUGAGUUACACCUUAUACAAAAAUUAAUUCAGGAUGGAGUAAAGACUUAAAUGUUAGACCUAAAACCAUAAAAACCCCAGAAGAAAACCUUGGCAAUACCAUUCAGGACAUAGGCAUGGGUAAGGACUUCAUGUCUAAAACACCAAAAGCAAUGGCAACAAAAGCCAAAAUUGACAAACAGGAUCUAAUUAAACUAAAGAGCUUCUGCACAGCAAAAGAAACCUACCAUCAGAUUGAACAGGCAGCCUACAGAAUGGGAGAAAAUUUUUGCAAUCUACUCAUCUGACAAAGGGCUAAUAUCCAGAAUCUACAAUGAACUCAAACAAGUUUACAAGAAAAAAACAAACAACCCCAUCAAAAAGUGGGCGAAGGAUAUGAACAGACACUUCUCAAAAGAAGACAUUUAUGCAGCCAAAAGACACAUGAAAAAAUGCUCACCAUCACUGGCCAUCAGAGAAAUGCAAAUCAAAACCACAAUGAGAUACCAUCUCACACCAGUUAGAAUGGCAAUCAUUAAGAAGUCAGGAAACAACAGGUGCUGGAGAGGAUGUGGAGAAAUAGGAACACUUUUACACUGUUGGUGGGACUGUAAACAAGUUCAACCAUUGUGGAAGUCAGUGUGGUGAUUCUUCAGGGAUCUGGAACUAGAAGUACCAUUUGACCCAGCCAUCCCAUUACUGAGUAUAUACCAAAAAUAUUAUAAAUCAUGCUGCUAUAAAGACACAUGCACAUGUAUGUUUAUUGCGGUACUAUUCACAAUAGCAAAGACUUGGAACCAACCCAAUGUCCAACAGUGAUAGACUGGAUUAAGAAAAUAUGGCACAUAUACACCAUGGAAUACUAUGCAGCCAUAAAAAAGGAUGAGUUCAUGUCCUUUGUAGGGACAUGGAUGAAGCUGGAAACCAUCAUUCUCAGCAGACUGUCACAAGGACAAAAAACUAAACACCGCGUGUUCUCACCCAUAGGGAAGGAAACUGAAAAGGCCAAGGAACGAUACGACAAAGCCACAAUGAAACUUCAUAUGUUGCACAAUCAGUAUGUAUUGGCGUUGAAAGGGGCACAGCUCCAUCAGAAUCAGUAUUAUGAUAUCACACUUCCCCUGCUUCUGGACUCCUUACAAAAGAUGCAAGAAGAAAUGAUAAAAGCACUCAAAGGUAUAUUUGAUGAAUACAGCCAGAUAACCAGUCUUGUCACAGAGGAAAUAGUGAAUGUCCAUAAAGAGAUUCAAAUGUCGGUUGAACAGAUAGAUCCUAGUACAGAAUACAAUAAUUUCAUAGAUGUUCACAGAACAACGGCUGCUAAAGAACAAGAAAUAGAGUUUGAUACUUCCUUACUGGAAGAAAAUGAAAAUCUUCAGGCAAAUGAGAUCAUGUGGAAUAACUUAACAGCAGAAAGUUUGCAAGUAAUGUUGAAAACGUUAGCGGAAGAACUUAUGCAAACACAGCAGAUGCUUUUAAACAAGGAGGAGGCUGUUUUGGAGUUAGAGAAGAGAAUUGAAGAAUCUUCUGAAACUUGUGAGAAGAAGUCUGAUAUUGUGCUUCUGCUAAGCCAAAAACAGGCACUUGAAGAACUGAAACAGUCAGUCCAGCAGCUGAGAUGCACUGAAGCAAAGUUUUCAGCACAGAAGGAAUUACUAGAGCAAAAAGUGCAAGAAAAUGAUGGGAAAGAGCCACCUCCAGUAGUAAAUUAUGAAGAAGAUGCACGAUCAGUUACAUCUAUGGAAAGAAAGGAGAGGCUAUCCAAAUUUGAAUCUAUUCGUCAUUCAAUUGCUGGAAUAAUUAGGUCUCCAAAAUCUGCACUGGGCUCUUCAGCACUUUCUGAUAUGAUCUCCAUCAGUGAGAAGCCUUUGGCAGAACAGGACUGGUACCAUGGUGCAAUUCCCAGAAUAGAAGCUCAAGAACUGUUAAAAAAACAAGGAGACUUUUUGGUGCGAGAGAGUCAUGGGAAACCUGGUGAAUAUGUCCUUUCUGUAUAUUCUGAUGGACAGAGGAGACAUUUUAUCAUACAAUAUGUUGAUAACAUGUAUCGAUUCGAGGGCACUGGGUUUUCAAACAUUCCUCAACUUAUAGAUCAUCACUAUACAACAAAACAGGUCAUCACUAAGAAAUCAGGUGUAGUUCUGCUGAAUCCUAUUCCUAAGGACAAGAAAUGGAUUCUCAGUCAUGAAGAUGUCAUAUUGGGAGAAUUACUGGGCAAGGGAAAUUUUGGUGAAGUAUAUAAGGGCACAUUAAAGGAUAAAACUUCUGUUGCUGUUAAAACAUGUAAAGAAGAUCUUCCUCAGGAAUUGAAAAUAAAAUUUUUACAAGAAGCCAAAAUUCUCAAGCAAUAUGAUCAUCCCAAUAUUGUCAAACUUAUAGGAGUUUGCACACAAAGACAGCCUGUCUACAUCAUUAUGGAACUGGUUUCAGGAGGUGAUUUCCUCACCUUUCUGAGAAGGAAGAAGGAUGAACUAAAACUCAAACAGUUAGUGAAAUUUUCAUUAGACGCUGCUGCUGGUAUGUUGUAUCUCGAGAGUAAAAACUGUAUACACAGGGACCUUGCUGCAAGAAACUGCCUGGUAGGUGAAAAUAAUGUUCUGAAAAUCAGUGACUUUGGAAUGUCUCGUCAAGAGGAUGGUGGAGUGUAUUCAUCUUCUGGCUUAAAGCAGAUUCCCAUUAAAUGGACAGCACCGGAAGCUCUUAAUUAUGGGAGAUACAGUUCAGAGAGUGACGUGUGGAGCUUUGGCAUCCUUCUCUGGGAGACCUUCAGCUUAGGGGUUUGUCCGUACCCUGGAAUGACAAAUCAGCAAGCAAGAGAGCAAGUAGAAAGAGGAUACCGGAUGUCAGCUCCCCAGCACUGUCCAGAGGAUAUUUCCAAAAUCAUGAUGAAGUGUUGGGAUUAUAAACCUGAAAAUCGCCCUAAGUUCAGUGAACUUCAGAAAGAGCUCACUAUCAUCAAGAGAAAACUCACAUAGUGACAGGAUGGCGCCAAACUCAGCCUUCAGGACUCUGUCCUCCAGCAGAGUAACAUUAUUGUUCUCAUUAACAAUGAAUUUAUACCACAUUACCUUCGACAGUCUUCUACCAUUAUUUUUUAUUAACUGGGUGUUUUAAAAGUACGUUCCACUUGUAAAAAGUCAAAGGCAAAUUUGUUAAAGAAAUAGGCAGUCCUACCAAGGGCUUUCUUAGCUAACCAUAGCAAUCCUACCAUUUCAGGCCAUUGCAAAUAGAAAAGCACAGGCUUCUAAGUGUGUGAAGGAUAAAAGAUCUAUCCUAUCCUUUUCACACCUUGUUUCUACUUCAGGCACAGUUUGUAGGCUGCCAUCCUAUGCCACAGACCCUACUCCGUUGGUGCUAUAAACAGCAUUGGUAAUGCCAUGUUUGCAGGACAUGUUCCAACCACAGCUGGCUUUCACCUCUGCCAAAGCAGGAUUAUAUUUGUAAACAAACAAACAGAAUUUUAUAUUGGGAAUUAUUUGGACCUCCUGAGAUUUUUCUUUUCUUUCUUGCCAGGUAUAAGCCCAAUGUAAGAAUCAUCAUGCUCCUACAUUAUUUGUAAGGUUGUCAUUUUCCUCCUCCUUUGUCUGGGCAUCAGAAAACAAUGCACGUAGGUCGGGCACGGUGGCUCACGCCUGUAAUCCCAGGCAUGUAAUCUCAUGCCUGGGAUUACAGGCGUGAGCCACAGUGCCCAGCCCCCUCCCUCCUUUGGGAGGCUGAGGCAGGCGGAUCACCUGAGGUCAGGAGUUCGAGACCAGCCUGGCUUGCAUGGUGAAACCCUGUCUCUACCAAAAAAAAAAAAAGAAACACACACACAACGCAUGAAACGUCGUCAAAGUUAGAGUUGAGGCAGUUGCUUUUCAAGGAUGUACAGAGAGCUGUGAAGCAAGAAACAGAUUUGAACAGGAGGGUGGGCUGGAGAACAGAGCAGCUAAAGAAUGAUUAACAGAGUAAAGAAGAAAGUGAAAAUAUAAAACCACCUUAUCAGAGUUAUGCCUUUCUAAACAUCUAAACAAACAAACAUUCACAUAUUCUAUUCUAAAAACACAUAAUAAUACAUAUUCUAUUUUAUGGUCUGAAUUUACCAGAAAGGUCCUAAGAAAAGUUUCAGGAGUUCGUAGAGUCCUCGUAAUGGCAACAAAAAUUUUGAGAGAAACUGCAAAGCACAAAUCCACAGAAAUAACAGCAUACUUUCAGUUAAGCAUUUUCACCUUAGAGGGGGCAUUCCAAAAUGUAAUUUCCUUUAUUUGUACCAGUUUUUAGAGCUGUCAGAAUUUCAUGAUUCUAGUUCACCAACACAUUCACGUGUGUACAUGCGCGUGCACACACACCACCAAGGUGCAAGACAGAUGUGAAUGAAGUAGACAGUCUAGAAGUCAGGUGAAUAUUAAUGAGAAAUAUGACAUAGGGACAGCCCUCCCAUUUCUACUUCCACCUUCAUUGACCAUUAUACUGCCCCCUGGACAUUCUUACCAUUAGCUGACAGGUAUGCAAGCAGAGUGCUGAAGAUGUCUCAUGUGAAUAAAAUGUAACUCACUCACUCAGUUAAAACUAGGAUUCUGUAUCUUAACUCUUAUCUAGGGAACUUACUUACUUACCCCAUGAUCUGUAUAUAGUUGCCUCUCAGGAUAAAUGCAUAUAUAGAAGAUGGUCAUGCUCAGGGCUAAAUAUGUUCUGGAAGCCUUUUAUAAGUUCUCAGGCCUGUGUCCUGGUAAACAUUACCUUAGUGAUUAUUUGGUCUGCAUUCAUUGGAAGAGCUUAGGGAUAGAAAAUGCCUCCUGCCCUCUCCAGCUGUUUGCUGCCUGUACCAUCGCACAGAACUCACACCAGUACUUUAGAGUAUGAAAGAUAAUACUGAAGAGAAAAGUGACUUGUAUCUAACAUUUCAAUCUCCUUGCAGAUUUCAUACAUACUUAAUGAUUAGUACAUUCAGACUAAAGGGAAAUUUCUUUUGAUGGCACGUACUAUGGUAAAUCAAAGCGCAAACUCAGAAGUGCUAUGGUAUUGAGGCACUUACCAACCUUCAAAAGUAAGAGUAAAAUGGGAUAUUCCUACCCUUUUUUUUAGUAUUUCUAAGUGAAUCUCUGUAAUAUUCUUUGUCUGUUUAAAGAAAACAGCCUCCCAUCUCAUAGUGGCUUCAUGCUAAGCUCUCAGCAAGGAGAGAGAAUGAUGGUUUUGGCUUUAGUUUUAUGAACAAGACCUAAAGCUUAAUCCUGACAUUCUGGUGUUAAGAAUGAACACAGCAUUGAUAUUUCACUUAUCCAGGCUGUUAGAAUUUGCAGUUCACAUCAUUACUCUGUGCUUAAAUUUAAAAAGCUUUUCAAAACAUCGUGACAUGUGUAGCAUUUAAAUUCCAUUUUAUUCUUUGUCCUAAAGCAGGCAGUGGUAUAGUUCAGGAUUAAUAACUUAUUGGGAGUCUCUCAGUCAUAUAGAAUAUUAAAUUUAAUAUAGUCACAUGCAUUAAGAAAAACUUACGCAAACAGUUUUUCACUGUUAAUUUUGUUGUGCUUGAAGCAUAAUUUAUUCAUCCCUUCUGUCACUGAUAAUUAAUUAUUGGAAUUAUAUACUUUAGGAGGCUAAUCCAUGCCCAGGAAGCACGAACAUACUGUUCAGAAUGUGCAAGUUGAUGUAGGGAAAGGAAGAUUCAGAAAUGUACAAAAUCCUGUGAUUUGUUUAGUAAGAAAAGAGUUGUAACCAAAAUUUCUUCUGGUCCGGAUGUAAUUAGUCCAGUCACAAAUCUUUGUGUUGUUAAUGGAUUAUUCAAGAUAUAUAUAUAUAUUCUUACUACUGCAUAGUUCCUCUCAUAAGUCCUUAAAUUUAUUAAAAGGGGGAGGUAAACACAAGCAGUCUGUGUCUCACUGGUCACUAAGGGGCCUUUAUGAGACAGUUUAGGUUGUUCAUCAUUUCACAAGGAAAGAAAUUUUUCACUGUUAAAUUAACAUUUAUUACCAACAUGUGAAACCUAAAAUUAAUUUUGCAUUCCAUGUAAUCUAAGGCCAAAGCCAACAUAUUCUUUCUCUUCUGGGAAAAUAAAAUUGACAGGUUUUGUUUAAACUUCAGAAACUGAAGCUUUAUUUCAGCCUGUCCUGCCAUGAGGUCUCCAGUGAGAGGUCUCCAGUGAAAGGUCUCAUGUAAUUGUUUCUCUUUUAUCUCCCAAAUUUAAUGUGGGCAAUAAAAUUCUCCUUUCGUAAUUCACUGUUUUAUUACAAAUACGAUAUUACUGAAACAUCUUAUUAGCAGAUAAGUAUAGACCAGGAGCCUAACUGUGUUAGAUAUUUUCAGUGCACAUUUCACAGUUGUUUUUCAUUUUAGGAUUAUUUUGAGAAGAAAAAAUGUUUUGUAAUUGAAAUAGUUUUAAUUUCCUUUAAACCAUAAUUUGGUUUUUCUAUCUAUAUUAUAUUCAGUUCAGUUUUCCCAUAUAACUUUUGUGAAGAUUGGCUAGUACCACAAAAUAACUAUGGCUUCACAAUACUAGUGUUAGAUUAUGUCAAGAAGAAAGUGUUUUAGUUACAACAUACGCCACCCACUGAGGACCUUGUAGUGGGAUAAACAAAAAUUAAAAUGCAACAAUCCAAAUAAAUUAUAAUGUAACAAUACAAAUAUCUGAAUCAUAAGUCACAGUUUUUCAGGGUUCUUUCAGUCACACCACUUUAUAAUUAAUUCUGGUGAGUCAUCAGAUGUAGGAAUGUACCUGAAAACCUUACUUAGUAUACUGUGUACACUGUUUAAUGGCCAUGCAUCUUUUGAAGUUUGAUAUUUUCUGAAAAAGCAUUGUUUGCCUCAGCCCUCUUCUUUUUACGUAUACUCCAUUUAUCAUUGAUAUUUUAGAUGUUUCUUAUCAACAAAAUUGGCUGCCCUGGUUAGUGCUGAGUCAUCGCAAGACUUGCUUUUGCAUUUAGGAAGCCACACCCUCCCACAAAACAGAACAGUGCAAAAUAAGCAGCAGAGAGACAGACAGUUGGAAAAGACAUGUUUUCUUUAGGUAUUAAUAUCUUAAUUAAAUGGAAUCAGAUUUUGUAUGGAAAUGAGUUUAUAUUACAUUUCCAUUAUACUAAGUCAGUGUGAAAGUUUACCAUCAAAAUAGCGUUACUUCUUUUAUGACUAACUCUGAUUUGCUUAUACAUAUCAGAAUGAUAUUCAUUAAAUAUUUUAAUUUCAUUUAUUUUUCUAUGUUUUGAUUAGUUUCACAUCAAGUCUGAAUACUAUAUUUUGGAAGAAUCCAAAACCACAUAUGAAGAUACUGAUUUUAAAAGUCAGGAUUUCAUGUACCAAGAAUGACCUACUUGAAGGAGAUUUUGCUACACUCUUAGAGUCCCAAAAAUUCCCCUUUAAAAAAAAUGCUGUCCUACAGAAGGUGUAUAAACUAUACCUUAGCCAUAAUUCAAUUUAAUGAAAUACUACCCCAUUAAAAGCCAUCCUCCUGCCUCAUACCGAUUCAGAAAUUAAAUUCUGAACUUUUAGUGUAGGCAUUAGGAAUCACUUAGCCACUUAAUAAGGACUGAGAUUCUUGGGUGGCAGAAAAAUCCUGGUGUGCUAGAUUCUUAGUCACUUUAAACUGCAUAGAAGUAAUGAGCAUAGGCUUCAGUAUAUUUAAUAAGGUGCUGAGGCAGCAGAUUCAAAUGCAAAAGAGGGAGGAACCAGUUAUUCCAAGGCAGGAUGAUGCACCCCCACACAGAGUGUGGAAAAAUUAAAGUGAAACAAAGAUUUGGACAGUGUCAUUAGGAAGCCUGAGGAGAACAUGCUACAAGGCCAGAUCCUGUCCUAUGGAAAAUAAAAAAGAUCAGCAGAACUAAAGCAAAAGCAGUCAUCUCCAGUGUGUGGGCCUUAGCAAAGAGUAAACCAAAUACCUCUCCUUGUGUUAGGAGCACUGUUAUAUUCCCAGCUCAGAGAUGAUUGUGUGCUGGGAAAUGCUUAUAUUCAUUAUUUCCCAACUAAUGCAUUUGGACAUAUGUAUUCCAGUUUUUCAAAGACACUACCCAAAGCUUCUUUACAUUUGCAUUGGUUAUAUUUAAUAUUUCUUAAGCUAAGAUCACUGAUUAUCCACACGUUAUUAGAAAUCUUUGGUUACAGUGAGGCUUAACCUGGGCUAAAGUCUCCUAAAUGGGACUACACUUAGAUCCGCCCUAUUUCACCUUUGGACUAACGUUGACUAAAUGGCUCCUAGAGUUACCCACAGAGGGAGCUUACUAUGAUGAGAGCUACUGUGGGGAAACAUAGUAUUCAACAGAGAAAUGGAAGAAUACAAGUAGCAAUGUUCCUUGUCUUCAAUAACAUUUGAGGGAAAGGAAUCUAGAAAUCCUAAAGCUUAGUCAGGGUGCCUAAGGUAAGACACAAAAAGAAAGAGACAUCCAGAAAGGAAGGUUGAAAGGAAAUGAAGGGCAGUAACAAAGCACCAAUGUAAAAUGACCCAUAGCCAACAAUAAAUGCAAUAACAAUAAAGGAAACUAACCCUCACAAAGGGUUUGAGGAGCUUCCUGCUGUGUGUCCUUAAACAGUGCGUGCCUCUUAAGUCUCUACAACACUUUUUUAAAGGGCAUUGAAUUGGACAUUGGUUUAAUUUUUACCUACGCUCCCUAUAAUCUCAGGAGGUAACCAUUAUUUAAUCAGAAUUACCCUUGCUCUGUUUAUCUGUGAGGCCUCAGACACAACGGUGGUUCAGCCCUCUCCCUAAGCAGUAGCAAGCUGAGUAAUGGCACACAUAUGUCUAGGAUAGCCAGCAUUCAGGAAAAUUGCUGUGAACCUCCUGUUUUUAAUUUUAAUAUAGAAAAAGUCUUUCAGGUUUGUGACACGAAGACAGAUUUAGCUUCCCACUUGUCAGCAAAUUUGUAAAAACCUCAAAACAAAUGAAUAUUUGGAAUUCACUCUAAGAGAUACAAAUCCUGAAUUUCUAACUAUCUUCUCAAAUAUUACUGAGGCCAGCAAGAUGCAAGUGUUCUACAAAAUAAUGAACUGUUCUAAGUGACAGUGUUGAUGCUGGAAGUGGAAUGUUAUGUUUUCGCUCAGCUGUAUUCAUUCAGAAAGUUUUUCUUGAACAUCUGCCACAUGAGGUGCAGAGAAUACUACCAGGUGCUAGUUUUUCCAGUAUUUGACUUCUGAUUACUAUUUCCUUUUCUCAUCUUUAGUUUUUCAAGAUUUUGCUUUACCAAAAUAGUAAAGCCUUUAUCAUCAGCUUAUAUUGAAUAAUGUUGUAAUUGGUUUCAAUCAAAGUUUCUCCUCAGGUACUUGGGGGCCCCUAGCCUUCUAAGGAACUCCCAGGCACCUACUUAACAAGGCCAGCUACACACUCAGUAUGUGAUAAGCCCCAUGAUGGAUGCAGGUUAGAAUUCAAAGACCUGGUUGGAGUCCUAGAUGUGGAGACAGGAUGAUCAGGUCACACUUGUUAGAUGACUAACACUAUCAGUAGAAGCUCUUGAGAGAUUUUCCUAACGCAGCAAGAUUUCUGUGAGUAGAGGUAUCCUGGGAGGUAUCCUGGGAGGCAGCCUAUUGACUUGACCAAGUAAGCUGAUCAGGUGGCCUCCUCUACCCACUAAAGAAAUGUGUAAACACUAGCAAUAAUUGCUUUAUCUUAAACUCCUGGACAUACUCAGUUCUUCCAUUCCACUGUUCUAUUGCCAAUACCUUUUGUUGUUUUCUUCACACUCCUCUUGGCAGCAAAUGUCUGAAAGUAUUUCAAUUGUGUAAUGUUAAGGAGUUUUUUCAUAGCUUCAGAAAAGAGGGCAGCAAAUAUGAAGCCUUAAGUUCAAAAUAAGUCAUUCUACCUAGAAAUACAGACCCCAGAGCACAUUGCAUGAAAAUACCUGUACUCUGCAGUUCCUCAAAGCAGUAUUCUUCCUGAAAAGCCAAACACCACACCUAUUUUCCUAUUUGCUAAGAAUCAGAAUAAGCACGUUGUAAAUAGUAUCCAAAGCAGAUUCUAAAAUGACAUAGUAAGAAGCCAGAUUCAAAUUGUAACCAAAGAAGACAAUAGAAAUCCCACUUUACCCCACUGUCAUCAGUUAGAACACCCUUGCAAAAACUGUAACCACUUAAGCAAUUCAUCUGAUCCCAGAAGAUCAUACCUUCUUUUGAAAGUAUAGGACAGAUAUCAGUGGGAAACGUCGGCGUUCUGAGCAACACAGGAUAAAUGUAGGAGGGCCUUAAAAAAUAAAUCUCAAUUCAUACACUGGAGCAGCAAAAAACUGAGCAGGAAAGGAAACAGAAUCCAAAGUCAUUUUUCAUAUAGCUGUUGUCAAAUAGUAUAACCUUGGUGUCUUCUUUGAGUUGCCUGGACAGUAUUUAUGAAACAAAAAACUAAAUGCCCCCCAUUUGGGGACGGGGGGAGGGGUUCAGACCUCUAACCUGGAUUCAGAGCCUUAGAGGCCGAGAGGGAAUCUGGAAUCUGGUAUUACUGAGAUCCUAGGUAAAAGAACCAGCCUGGCAGUCUUUCCCACCUCAUUGGUCCGUGCUUUUAUUUUUAAACCCAAAAGAAAGAAAGAAACACACCCUCUUAUGUAGGAAUUUCCCUUUUACAAAUAAUUUGACCUGGUAGAAAUAAACUUGCCUGCCUGCUCUUAAAUGCCAGACAGUUGGAAGCAAAUGCCGAGGGAAAGGUGCCCAGAGCCAUGCUUGAUAGGACUUUGAAUAUUUUCUCCUUAAUUAAAGUACGUUGCUUGUAUUUAGACUAUAAGAUGCUAUGGAGGUCUAUCCCAUGCCAUGCCAAUGUGAAUUGCUUUGCUUCAGUAACAAUCAGAAGACCAGUCCAACAGAAAAUAACUUGUCAUAAUUCCACCUUAGAUUCUAGACCUCUCAUACCUGCAGUGUACAGAAUAUGUACAUGUUCCAAUGGAAUUCACUAUUUUUGGCUUUAGUGUCAAAGAGAUUGGUUCUACAAGGUUCAUCUGAUUUCCCAUAACAAGUAAAUUUUAUAAUCCUAUGAUUCUAAAUUCAAUCCCCAAUAUAGAUUCUAAGCAUCAAAUCAAAAUCACAGACAAAGGGGAACUGGUCGAGAGGGGUCUUAGUUAUUUCAAAUCCAUGACCAAAGUGUCCAAAGACAUGAAACUCUUAUACCUGCUGAGCAUUUCACUUUACUAUACAAAAUGUCAGCUACCCAGUUGCAUCCUGUGACAUGAUCAGACUGUCAAUGUGGACCAGUGGCCAGGAGCAUAUUUAUGGGCCAUUUCUGUUCAUCAUUCUUUACAGAGCAUUGAGGUUUCCCACUGAAACAGCUUCUUUAGUCAGACGUCUAUAGAUUUUACAUAAAUUUACAUUUAAAUGCAUUAAGUUAGAUGGCCCAAUUGAGCAUCUGAAUGAAUAUAGUGGGGGUUGGUGGUGGUGCAAAUUCUGCUGGCUUUAUGUUAUGGUUUUCUUCGUGUUUUUUCUUGGUUUUGUCUGGCUUCUUCUGGCAAGUGCCCUAAAAGACUGGAACACUGUAUAAAGUCAUAGACAUAGAACCAUAUGGGAAAGCCCAGAUGAAAAAAUGGAAGAAUAAAAUCAAGUUGUCAAAGUUCCAGCAACAGCCCUGACUUCUUCAGGAAUCCAAGCAAAUUGAAAGCCAAGACAAAAUGUACAAAUGGUGCCCAUGCCAUUCAUUUGACUGUGGGUGGCCCUCUAGUCUAGGGCUCUCUUAGUGAAUGGUUGUGGAAAUAUGAUUUUUCUAAGUUCCUUCCUUUUCCUUUUGAUAGAUGAGUUUGAGAUGAUGGAGUAGGAGUGGGGCCCUCAGGCACUUCUGGUAAAGACAUUCCACCUGCAAGCAGCAUUUUGAGUAAAGCACUGCUGUGGUUUGCCGAUUUAUGGUCCAUUUAAUGUUAGGCUAAAGCACCUUUAAUCAUUUUUGUUGUUUUAAGAUAAUGUAUUUGUGAAGUGGAUAAACACUGGAAAUAGGGUGCUUCUUCUGGAAAGUUCAGUGUAAAACACAAACAAGGCUUUGGCGGGUUUAUCUGGCUUUAUAAACAAGUCUGAAAAAUGGAUGAAAGCUAAAUAUAUAAAGCAGUUGGUUGUCUAUCUUUUAUCAUUUUUACUCAGAUCUGUAUUUAACACUUAUUUAUUUGUUAGUUUUUACAUUCAAAAGAAAUACACUUUGAACUUUGGCUAACAUUGUAGGAUAUUUUUUAAUUGUUUCUACAUUUUUAAAGCAUGAUUCAUCAUUUUUGUAAACUUAGAUCAUUUUUUAAUUGUCUUUUCUUUUCCAAUAGACCAGUUACCACUCAUGUGUCUGCAGAACCUCUUUAUUGUAUUCCUAUAAUAAAUGUAAAAUAUUUGUAGCAAA